AGAGCCAGCAGAGCAGGCUGACGACCUGCAAGCCACAGUGGCUGCCCUGUGCGUGCUGCGAGGUGGGGGACCCUGGGCAGGAAGCUGGCUGAGCCCCAAGACCCCGGGGGCCAUGGGCGGGGAUCUGGUGCUUGGCCUGGGGGCCUUGAGACGCCGAAAGCGCUUGCUGGAGCAGGAGAAGUCUCUGGCCGGCUGGGCACUGGUGCUGGCAGGAACUGGCAUUGGACUCAUGGUGCUGCAUGCAGAGAUGCUGUGGUUCGGGGGGUGCUCGUGGGCGCUCUACCUGUUCCUGGUUAAAUGCACGAUCAGCAUUUCCACCUUCUUACUCCUCUGCCUCAUCGUGGCCUUUCAUGCCAAAGAGGUCCAGCUGUUCAUGACCGACAACGGGCUGCGGGACUGGCGCGUGGCGCUGACCGGGCGGCAGGCGGCGCAGAUCGUGCUGGAGCUGGUGGUGUGUGGGCUGCACCCGGCGCCCGUGCGGGGCCCGCCGUGCGUGCAGGAUUUAGGGGCGCCGCUGACCUCCCCGCAGCCCUGGCCGGGAUUCCUGGGCCAAGGGGAAGCGCUGCUGUCCCUGGCCAUGCUGCUGCGUCUCUACCUGGUGCCCCGCGCCGUGCUCCUGCGCAGCGGCGUCCUGCUCAACGCUUCCUACCGCAGCAUCGGCGCUCUCAAUCAAGUCCGCUUCCGCCACUGGUUCGUGGCCAAGCUUUACAUGAACACGCACCCUGGCCGCCUGCUGCUCGGCCUCACGCUUGGCCUCUGGCUGACCACCGCCUGGGUGCUGUCCGUGGCCGAGAGGCAGGCUGUUAAUGCCACUGGGCACCUUUCAGACACACUUUGGCUGAUCCCCAUCACAUUCCUGACCAUCGGCUAUGGUGACGUGGUGCCGGGCACCAUGUGGGGCAAGAUCGUCUGCCUGUGCACUGGAGUCAUGGGUGUCUGCUGCACAGCCCUGCUGGUGGCCGUGGUGGCCCGGAAGCUGGAGUUUAACAAGGCAGAGAAGCACGUGCACAACUUCAUGAUGGAUAUCCAGUAUACCAAAGAGAUGAAGGAGUCCGCUGCCCGAGUGCUACAAGAAGCCUGGAUGUUCUACAAACAUACUCGCAGGAAGGAGUCUCAUGCUGCCCGCAGGCAUCAGCGCAAGCUGCUGGCCGCCAUCAACGCGUUCCGCCAGGUGCGGCUGAAACACCGGAAGCUCCGGGAACAAGUGAACUCCAUGGUGGACAUCUCCAAGAUGCACAUGAUCCUGUAUGACCUGCAGCAGAAUCUGAGCAGCUCACACCGGGCCCUGGAGAAACAGAUUGACACGCUGGCGGGGAAGCUGGAUGCCCUGACUGAGCUGCUUAGCACUGCCCUGGGGCCGAGGCAGCUUCCAGAACCCAGCCAGCAGUCCAAGUAGCUGGACCCACGAGGAGGAACCAGGCUACUUUCCCCAGUACUGAGGUGGUGGACAUCGUCUCUGCCACUCCUGACCCAGCCCUGAACAAAGCACCUCAAGUGCAAGGACCAAAGGGGGCCCUGGCUUGGAGUGGGUUGGCUUGCUGAUGGCUGCUGGAGGGGACGCUGGCUAAAGUGGGUAGGCCUUGGCCCACCUGAGGCCCCAGGUGGGAACAUGGUCACCCCCACUCUGCAUACCCUCAUCAAAAACACUCUCACUAUGCUGCUAUGGACGACCUCCAGCUCUCAGUUACAAGUGCAGGCGACUGGAGGCAGGACUCCUGGGUCCCUGGGAAAGAGGGUACUAGGGGCCCGGAUCCAGGAUUCUGGGAGGCUUCAGUUACCGCUGGCCGAGCUGAAGAACUGGGUAUGAGGCUGGGGCGGGGCUGGAGGUGGCGCCCCCUGGUGGGACAACAAAGAGGACACCAUUUUUCCAGAGCUGCAGAGAGCACCUGGUGGGGAGGAAGAAGUGUAACUCACCAGCCUCUGCUCUUAUCUUUGUAAUAAAUGUUAAAGCCAGAA